AGCGGGACCGAGCGUGACCCAGCUGCGGCCGGCCAGCCAUGGAGACUGGAGCGCUGCGGCGCCCGCAACUUCUCCCGUUGCUGCUGCUGCUCUGCGGCCCUUCCCAGGAUCAAUGCCGACCUGUACUCCAGAAUCUGUUGCAGAGCCCAGGCUUGACAUGGAGCUUGGAAGUGCCCACUGGGAGAGAAGGAAAGGAAGGUGGGGAUCGGGGACCAGGGCUAAGUGGGGCCACUCCAGCCAGGAGCCCUCAGGGCAAGGAGAUGGGGAGACAAAGGACCAGAAAGGUGAAGGGCCCUGCUUGGAGUCACACAGCAAAUCAGGAACUAAACAGGAUGAGGUCUCUGUCUUCUGGCUCCGUGCCAGUGGGGCAUCUGGAGGGUGGCACGGUCAAGCUUCAGAAGGACACGGGCCUCCAUUCCUGCAGAGAUGGUGGGUGUCCCAGAGCAGGCGGCUGCAACGAGACAGGCAUGUUGGAGAGGCUGCCCCUGUGUGGGAAGGCUUUCGCAGACAUGAUGGGCAAGGUGGACGUCUGGAAGUGGUGCAACCUGUCCGAGUUCAUCGUGUACUAUGAGAGUUUCACCAACUGCACCGAGAUGGAGGCCAAUGUCGUGGGCUGCUACUGGCCCAACCCCCUGGCCCAGGGCUUCAUCACCGGCAUCCACAGGCAGUUCUUCUCCAACUGCACCGUGGACAGGGUCCACUUGGAGGACCCCCCAGACGAGGUUCUCAUCCCGCUGAUCGUUAUACCCGUCGUUCUGACUGUCGCCAUGGCUGGCCUGGUGGUGUGGCGCAGCAAACGCACCGACACGCUGCUGUGAGGGUCCCGGUGAGAUGGAGUGGGUCACACCUGGCAAGCUGGAAGAAAGUUCCCUGGGGAUGGGAGAGCGGGUGGGUGCUGCCAAUCUCCAGCUACUGUGGCCACACCCCACCUGGUCAUGGGCAGACCCCUCCCUUCCUGGGCUGACCUGCUCCCUCGAGGCCAGCCUGCUCCCUGGCUGAGGCUCAGGCUAUCCGCCCAAGCUCUUUGCUCAUUCUAGGGCCAGUGGAGGAAAAUGUGAUAAGGCCAGAGCUUGUGUGCUGGGCACAGAAAUCACCUGCUGCAUCCUGUGCUCCGCAGGCUGGGCCGGAGCCUCUGCCCGCAGGUUUCUAUGCUGUUUCUUAGCACAGAAUCCAGCCUAGCCUUAGCCGCAGUCUAGGCCCUGCUUGGACUAGGACUCCUUGCUUGACCCCAUCUCUGGUUCCUGCCCUGGCUCCUGCACCAGCCCCAGCUCCUGCCUACAUCCAGGCAGAAAGAUAGGCAGGGGCUCUUGGAAGACGUUCCGUGCUGUGACCUCCGAGCCCUCCUGGUGGGAAGACAGCUGGAAAGGCUGGGAGGAGAAGGGAGGGGCUGGGGGUUCCCAGGAGCCAUGCGUGGCCUGCAGAGUCCAUUCCAUCAUGAUGCUGUGCCCGCUAUGGGCUGUGUCCAUGACCAGAGGCUGGAGUGGGGGUGUGUUAGAGCCCCUCACCGGGACUUGCUGUGCGGAUGGGGCCUGGGCCUCCUUCCUACAGGGGCUCCUCUGUGGGUGAGGGGCCCUCUGGAAUGGCAUCCCAUGAGCUUGUGGCCUCUAUCUGCUACCAUCUGUGUUUUAUCUGAGUAAAGUUACCUUACUUCUGGAA